AAUCCUGCCGCCGCCACCCACCCGCAACCGCGUCCGUUGACGGUCGGGUCCUUGGUCGCCGGGUCCUUGCGGGCACCACAGAGCGGGGUGGCGUCCGCUCCCUCGAGUCCUCGGUGCCAGGGAAUUCACCGCUCACCACCCCCUGCCCCGCCUUGGGUCCUGCUCGGGGACCAAACCACUGGAAGGCAGUGGCGGGAAACGGGCGCCUGUGCCGGAGGUCCUGAUGAGGGGGGUCCAAGGCUUGGGGACUUGUGCGGGAAAUAUAAUCCUGAUGUAAACCAUUGACAUAGCCAGAAAAUCACCAGGCUGUGAUUUUCCAAACUCAGCUUCAUAACCUAUUCUGUAGUUGAGGGAACAUGAGCCAUUUGCAGAGCUUAUUGUUAGACACCCUCUUGGGAACCAAGCAUGUGGACAGUGCAGCCCUCAUCAAAAUCCAGGAGCGGAGCUUGUGUGUAGCAUCACCAGGUUUCAAUGUAACGCCCAGUGAUGUCCGAACACUGGUGAAUGGAUUUGCCAAGAACCCUUUGCAAGCCCGAAGAGAAGGACUGUAUUUCAAGGGAAAAGAUUACAGAUGUGUCCGGGCAGAUGAAUAUUCUCUUUAUGCCAAAAAUGAGAACACUGGUGUGGUUGUCGUGAAGACCCAUCUGUAUCUUCUGGUAGCAACUUACACUGAGGGCAUGUAUCCUAGCAUCUGUGUGGAAGCCACAGAGAGCCUGGGAGACUACCUAAGAAAAAAAGGAAGUUAAGUCAUCAGAGGCCCAUGAAAGACAAUUUUAUUAUUUUAGAAGAAAAUUGAAGAGCCUAAAGAAAAAAUAUUUUAUGGUUGAAAAAACACUAGACAGAAGGCACUAAAAAAGAAGAAUGAAUUAAGGGAGCAAUUUUUAUUACUUCCAGAGAUCCUCUUCUUUCACUGGAAUUACUUGAUCAACUGUUUUUUAAUAAGUGUUGGUCAUCGGCAUGGAAUGAGAGAGCACUGAUCAUUUCACAGAGCAUAUCUAUUGGGAGGCUCCUUUCUGUGAGGCUCUUGUACUCCUACACACCUUGCUAAGUAUGCCAAGAAUGCAAGGCUCUCACCACUCUUUAUCCAAGACAUUUCUCAGGGUUAGGUUGCAGCAAGCAACCUUGAAAAAUGAAGGGAUGUCUCCCAUCAGGACAGAGAGCAAGCUUGCUUACUGUUUGCUAUAAAAGCAGUGGAGUCCCUGAGCUCAGUGUUACCCCUCCUGUAAUACAACUCCCUGCAUGUGUGACAUCUGUCUGGCUCACAUCACCCCGGUGAGACUUGGGAGAAGGGAUUGCAAAGGCCAUUCAACAAUGGACCACUAGUCAAGGUAUUCAAUGGACAUUUCACACUCCCAUUUGCAGGUAUCUGGUAUCAUUUUGAACAUUGGAAAGGCCUUCUCAAAAAUCAACUCAAAAAGAUUUCUGACUCUAACCCUAACUCUCACUGCACACCUUAGUAAGGCAGUAUGGUCACUAAAUGCACCCUUCCCCAGAAAGAGUUCAUCUCCUCUUGGUCUCCU